UUUCUAUUGUCUUUUUUCUUCACCAUUGGUCAAGUGGGUCACAUUUCCUUGUUUCUUUGUGUGUCAUGUAAAUUUGGAUUGUAUCCUGGACAUUGUGAUUUUAGUGUUGUGGAGACUCUGUAUUCUGUUAUUUUCCUCUGAAGAGUGUUGACUUUUUUAGCAGGUAACUAACUUAAUGGGAUAUAAACUAUAAACUAUCAGUUUAUUGAAUAUCAGUUUAGUUCUUGAAUCCCUAGUUGGGUUUUUGUUGUUUGCAUGCAGGCUUUCACAUGUGUGGUUCAGAGAUCAGCUAGAUAUUUGGGCAGAGGUAAAUAGGUGAUAUCUCCUUUACUGUGGCUCUCUCUUUCUCACAGUUCUCCCUUCACUUUCUAGCAGCUAUAAUUGCUUUUAACUAGGUAUUUUGGCAUUUUGGGUCAAUCAAGCUGUGAGUAUGCUAUUGGAGUCUUUAAUCACUAAUUGUAUGGGGUGUUCCUCACACAUAGUGUUUAAUAAACAUAAUUAAACCAAAAUGGAAUGUUGAGCAUAAAGUGUUAAGUUUUAAAAAGAUAUGUAUAGUGUGGUAUUAAUUAUAGAAAAUUAAAAAACAUGUAAAAUAAUAUAUGUUGCUUAUGGAAAUAGACAUAUAUGGUGUGUAUGUAAUUACCCUAUCUAAAAUUUUAUCUCAUUCAAAAUUUCAAACCCUUCAAUACAAACUUUCUCCUUCCCUUUGUGUAAUAUUUUUCUUUUUAGUACUUGUCAGCACUGAAUAUAUUAUGUUUUACUUACUUAUUUUUUGUCUUUCCACUAGAAUAUUAGUUUUAAGAAGCAGAUUUUUUUUUUUGUCUUCUCUGUUUGCUACAUUAUAACAAGUUCCUAGAGCAGUGUUUGACAUACAUAGGCACUCAAUAAGUAGUUGCUGAACAAAUAAAUAAAUAAUAUAAAAUAUAAGGACAUAACCACAAAUUUAGAAUAAUUUUUUAUGGGGGCUUCUAAUGUCUCUAAAAUGUUUUUUUCUGAAAAGUAAAACAAUGCAACAUGACAAAAUAUUAAGAUUUGAUGAGACUGGGUAGUGGUAACAUUAGUGUUCAUGAUUUUUAAAAUAUUUCUAUGUUUGAAUUACUUCAUUAAACAAUAGAAUGGGCAAAAAGUUUGGAGAAGACUUUGAAGAGCAUUAUGUUAUAGAAGUCAAGGGAAGAGGGAAUUUCAAAAAGAAAUAGGGAGAAAUUUCAAAUGCUGGCAUUAGUCACCAAGAGAUAAAGCAAUUAUAAUUUACUAUUAGGAAAUUAUUAGUGACUAUUGAAGUAACCUGUUUCAGCCACAAUUUGAUAGCAGGUAGGGUAGUGAGGAAAUGGAGAAAUGGAGGCCACUUAUUCAGUAAGAUGAUAGGCACAGCUUUUUGAGGAUGAAAAAUUUAUGCAUGUUUGCAAGCAGGAUGGGAAAAUCCAUUGAAAAGAUGAGACUUAAAAUGCUGGGAAAAAGAAGAUAAUUAAAAUAGCAAAUUCUAGAAUAAGUAGAAAUGUUUAUAAUUAGAGGCAUAGGUUUGGAAAAAAAGGCAUUGCAUCUGGCAAUGAGAAGAGGCACUACCUCUGCAAUAGAAGAAAACUAAGCAGGAAGGAUUGAGAUAGGUGGAGACAGAAGGAAAGGUGAGGGAGUUCAUUGAAGUAGUAAGGCCAUAUGUCGGAAUGGUGAAACUGAGUAAUGGAUAUGGCCCAGGUUAGUGAGUUAAUGGGCAUGUCAGAAGGCUCAAGCUGUGAGUGCCUAGGUUGAUGAUUAGAGUCUCAAUUAUAUGGGUGCUAUCAGGCUUUGGAGGCUCCGAAGCAUCAGAACUAACCUGAAUGGAUUGGGUGCAUUUGAGGAGUUUCAGCAGUAAUGCUAAUAGCAGCCAUCACUCAUAUGUGUCAUUGUUCUAGAUUCUCAUAUAUAUACUUAUUUAUUCCUGACAACCUUUAAUGUGACUAUGAUAUGACCAUUUUUCAGGUAAGGCAGUCGAGGCAUGGAGAAGUUAAGUAACUUGCACCAGGUUACACAGAUCAUGAGAGGCAAAGCUGGAAUUCAAACCCAGGCUGUCUAACUCCUCAGUCCAUGACUUAACACCAUUAUACUCUCCCUUAACUCAGUAACGGGAGGGUUAAUUGAUGACAAAUGAAAGAUUGUUAAGCAGAUAAAGGGAUAAUAGGUUUCCAACACAUACUUUGUCCUUUGUUUCUGUAUUAUCCAAGACACCUCUUUUUCAUGUGUGUUAAUUUCCAAUUACUGUUUUCUUUAUCAAAGCCUCAGGCUUCCAAGAAUUUUCUGAAUAACCCAUUGAGCUUUCUUUUAGUCAUACAAAGUGUUUGUCAUCUUCUCAGGAAUGUUCAUUAUAUUCAUAUUUUCUUUAGAAUGAUUCCAAUUUCUUUUUACUCAGAACGAACUCUUUGGCAUCAUGCUUCACAUAAUCAUUUAUCUUUUACUAAUAAAUGGAACUUCUCUUUGGGAUGUGGUUUUGGGAAUGAACAAUGACAUGGAAUGAUAGCUGAUUAGCCAGAGCAACCUGCCAAUCAGCAGGAUGUCAGAGUCCAAUCACAUAUGCAACCCAAAGAGCCAAUUCACUAACCCUUUAUGAACAUUUUUGCAAAUACCAUGAAACUUGAGUGCUGUGUGUGCAUCAUUAUGGGCAGUUUCCCUGUUAUUUGUAGAUUUUUUUAUUUGCUACUCAGAAGCAUCUUUCCUUGAUGUUUGUUCAUAAUAUUUUUCUUAAUUGUCCAAGAUUUCACCUGAAUAGUUUGAUAUAUUACACAGAAUUUAAAAUUCUUUCCCUAAAUAGGAUCUUUUAUUCUCUGAGGUGGAAAACAUUGAUUUAUCAGCAUUAAAAGUCAUUGUCAACACUUACCGUUUUGUUCCUGUAACUUUUACUAAAUUAACCUGCUAUGACCAUGCCCCUCAGCUUUAACAAAUUAAACUAUUUGAAUGAAGAAUGGACAUAAUGGUUGGGGAUUGUGCCGUACUUUUAGUUUACAAGGACUUGCGCAUCCAUUCGAUCUGCCCAGUAACUCUUCAGGUGACAGGGCAAGGUUUUAAUGUUCCCAUUUUACAGAUAAAGAACCGGAGGUGUAGGGAGAUUAGAAGAUGGUCCUUGAGUGAGUAAGUGGUAAAAGUGGGUCUUGAAUCUGGUUCUUCCCGACUCCAAGUGUCUCUCCAUUCUGUAGUGGAUUCUUUGGAUAUCUUCCUAUUAAUAUGCACGAUGCCCUCGUCUAUUGCCUUCCUUUCCCGCUGCCUUCGGUUUUCCAGUCGAGGGGCUUCCUAAUGUGUCCCUGUCCAGCUGGGAUGGCUGCAAGGGAGCACACCUGGGGUCUUCCUGUCUUCAGUCUUUCAUCUUCCUUUUCUGUGGCCCUUCCAGCUUCACCAUCCGUGGACAUCUCCUCCUUCCUUCAGCCCCAACUUCUAAAGUCUUGUCACAGCCCCCUGGCAGUGGGACCUCCCAUCCCCAAUCAUCAGCAGGAGAGCCCAUCGCAGAGGGGAGGCGAGGGCAGGGACCGCAGCGCACAGGGAAGCCAUGCUGAGGGUUCCUCCUGCAUUUUCUUCCUCGCGGUCCUCAGGAACAUCCUCGCGCCCUCCGGCCCCGGCGCUCCAGCCCGCCCCGGAUCCGCCUCCCUCUCCUUCCUCCCCGAGGUUGAGACGAAGCGUGGGACGCACCUGGGUCCCUCUCUGGUCACCCUGCUGAGGCUCCGGGGGCUGCUCCGGGAGCAGGAUUUACAGGCCCGGAGAACGCCAAUGGGAGAUCCAAAUGGUCGGGGACUCCGGCGCUUUAAGAGGCUUUUCUCUGGGAAACACCCGUCCCCUCCGUGCGCCUUAUGAAUGGAAAUACUCCUCCCCCGGUCGAGCCCAUUUUCCCAUUUCACCAGGAGCCGCAGCCUGCUCUCUCCUUUCGGUCUCCCCGCCCACAUCAACGCGGGCAGCUCCAGGAGGGGACGGACAGGAAGCCUUUGGCCGCCUAUUAAAUCCCACCCAUUUCUCCGGGGGCGAUUUCCUAACCUUCCGGGACCGAAUUCUGCAAUUUGAUUUGCUUCCAAGAUCCGGUACUUGCAGGAAUAUCAUAACCGGGUUCUCCACAACAUUUAUCCUGUACCAUCAGGAACAGAUAUUGCAAACACCUUGAAAUACUUUUCUCAGACCUUGUUAAGCAUUUUGUCCCGCACAGGGAAGAAGGAAAACCAAGAUGCCUCCAAUUUGACAGUGCCCAUGACCAUGUGUCUUUUUCCUGUGCCAUUCCCACUCACCCCAUCUCUAAGACCGCAGGUCAGUUCCAUCAACCCUACUGUUACUCGCUCCCUCCUUUACAGCGUCCUGCGAGAUGCUCCCUCAGAACGCGGCCCGCAAAGUCGUGAUGCUCAGUUGUCAGACUACCCUUCUUUGGACUACCAAGGCCUCUACGUGACUUUGGUGACCCUCCUGGAUCUAGUUCCUUUACUACAGCACGGCCAACACGAUCUUGGACAGUCGAUAUUUUAUACAACUACAUGUUUGCUACCUUUUCUCAAUGAUGAUAUUCUGAGUACUUUGCCCUACACGAUGAUAUCAACGUUGGCUACCUUUCCUCCAUUUCUGCACAAGGAUAUCAUUGAAUAUCUUAGCACAUCUUUUCUACCAAUGGCUAUAUUGGGCUCCUCAAGGAGAGAAGGUGUACCUGCCCAUGUUAACCUCUCUGCAUCAUCCAUGCUAAUGAUUGCAAUGCAGUACACAUCCAAUCCAGUGUAUCAUUGUCAAUUACUGGAAUGCCUCAUGAAAUAUAAACAAGAAGUCUGGAAAGAUCUUUUGUAUGUGAUUGCGUAUGGGCCUUCACAAGUGAAGCCUCCAGCUGUGCAAAUGCUUUUCCACUACUGGCCCAAUUUAAAACCUCCUGGGGCAAUAAGCGAGUACAGGGGGUUGCAGUACACAGCUUGGAAUCCCAUCCACUGCCAGCACAUUGAAUGCCACAAUGCAAUUAACAAACCAGCUGUGAAGAUGUGUAUAGACCCUUCCCUGUCAGUAGCGUUGGGUGAUAAACCACCCCCGUUGUAUCUCUGUGAAGAAUGCAGCGAGAGGAUUGCAGGGGACCACAGUGAGUGGCUGAUUGAUGUUCUUCUGCCACAAGCUGAAAUAUCUGCUAUAUGUCAGAAAAAGAACUGCAGUUCCCACGUUAGAAGAGCAGUUGUCACCUGCUUCUCAGCAGGGUGCUGUGGUCGUCACGGAAACAGGCCUGUUCGGUACUGCAAGAGGUGCCACUCAAAUCAUCACAGUAAUGAAGUGGGGGCCGCUGCGGAGACUCACCUCUAUCAGACCUCUCCUCCGCCCAUCAACACGCGGGAAUGCGGCGCUGAGGAGCUGGUCUGCGCCGUGGAAGCCGUGAUCAGCUUGUUGAAAGAAGCCGAGUUCCAUGCUGAGCAGCGAGAACAUGAGCUGAACCGGCGGCGGCAGCUGGGCCUCUCCUCUUCCCACCAUUCCCUGGAUAAUGCUGACUUUGAUAACAAGGACGAUGAUAAACACGAUCAGAGGCUGCUCAGUCAAUUCGGAAUAUGGUUCUUAGUGAGCCUCUGCACACCCAGUGAGAACACGCCUACAGAAAGCUUGGCCCGGCUGGUGGCCAUGGUGUUUCAGUGGUUUCACUCCACUGCGUAUAUGAUGGAUGAUGAAGUGGGAAGUCUGGUGGAAAAGCUGAAGCCUCAGUUUGUCACCAAAUGGCUGAAGACCGUAUGUGAUGUUCGCUUCGAUGUCAUGGUCAUGUGCCUUCUUCCUAAACCCAUGGAAUUUGCCAGGGUUGGUGGCUACUGGGAUAAGUCCUGUAGCACAGUGACUCAGCUGAAGGAAGGUCUCAACCGAAUCCUCUGCCUGAUCCCCUAUAAUGUGAUCAAUCAAUCUGUCUGGGAGUGUAUUAUGCCGGAAUGGCUGGAAGCCAUCAGAACAGAAGUCCCAGAUAAUCAGUUAAAAGAAUUCAGGGAAGUAUUAAGCAAAAUGUUUGACAUUGAACUCUGUCCUCUGCCUUUCUCAAUGGAGGAGAUGUUUGGUUUUAUUAGUUGUCGGUUUACAGGAUACCCCUCCUCUGUGCAGGAGCAAGCUUUACUGUGGCUUCAUGUAUUAUCGGAGUUAGAUAUCAUGGUUCCACUUCAACUACUAAUAAGUAUGUUUUCUGAUGGAGUUAAUUCAGUCAAAGAGCUGGCAAAUCAAAGAAAAUCAAGAGUCAGUGAACUGGCAGGGAACCUUGCAUCUCGAAGGGUGAGUGUUGCCUCUGAUCCUGGCCGACGAGUUCAGCACAAUAUGCUUAGUCCAUUUCAUAGUCCUUUCCAGAGUCCGUUUCGGAGUCCUUUGCGUAGUCCGUUUCGUAGCCCUUUCAAGAAUUUUGGACACCCAGGAGGAAGGACUAUUGACUUUGAUUGUGAAGAUGAUGAAAUGAAUCUAAAUUGUUUCAUCCUCAUGUUUGAUCUUCUCCUGAAGCAGAUGGAGUUACAAGAUGAUGGAAUCACGAUGGGUUUAGAGCACAGCUUAUCAAAGGACAUUAUUUCUAUUAUAAACAAUGUCUUCCAAGCCCCCUGGGGGGGAUCCCACACCUGCCAGAAGGACGAAAAAGCAAUCGAGUGCAACUUAUGUCAGUCUAGUAUCCUCUGCUAUCAGCUUGCUUGUGAACUCCUGGAGAGACUAGCUCCUAAAGAAGAAAGCCGGCUGGUGGAGCCCACAGACAGCCUGGAGGAUAGCCUCCUUUCUUCCAGACCAGAGUUUAUCAUAGGCCCUGAAGGGGAGGAGGAGGAGAAUCCUGCAAGCAAGCAUGGGGAGAACCCAGGCAACUGCACCGAGCCCGUGGAACAUGCUGCAGUAAAGAAUGAUACCGAAAGAAAAUUUUGCUACCAACAGCUUCCGGUAACAUUGAGACUAAUAUAUACCAUUUUCCAGGAAAUGGCUAAGUUUGAAGAGCCAGACAUUCUUUUUAAUAUGCUCAAUUGCCUGAAGAUUCUCUGUCUGCAUGGAGAAUGUUUAUACAUUGCCAGAAAAGAUCACCCUCAAUUUUUAGCCUACAUUCAGGACCACAUGUUGAUUGCAAGCCUGUGGAGGGUCGUCAAAUCCGAGUUCUCUCAGCUGUCUUCCCUGGCAGUCCCUCUUCUCCUCCAUGCCCUGUCACUUCCUCAUGGUGCUGACAUCUUCUGGACAAUCAUAAAUGGCAAUUUCAACAGCAAAGACUGGAAGAUGAGGUUUGAAGCAGUGGAAAAAGUUGCUGUAAUUUGUAGAUUUCUGGAUAUUCACUCAGUAACCAAAAACCACCUGCUGAAGUACUCCCUGGCACAUGCCUUCUGCUGCUUCCUGACAGCAGUGGAGGAUGUCAACCCCGCAGUGGCUACCAGAGCUGGUCUCCUGCUUGACACCAUAAAGAGGCCAGCAUUGCAGGGUCUAUGUCUUUGUCUUGACUUCCAGUUUGAUACUGUGGUUAAAGACAGACCCACAAUUUUGAGCAAGCUUUUACUCUUGCACUUUCUUAAGCAGGAUAUUCCUGCUCUGAGCUGGGAGUUCUUUGUCAAUAGAUUUGAGACGCUUUCUUUGGAAGCCCAGCUACAUUUGGAUUGUAACAAGGAAUUUCCUUUUCCUACAACCAUCACUGCUGUGAGGACCAAUGUUGCUAACCUCAGCGAUGCAGCCUUAUGGAAGAUCAAGAGAGCUCGCUUUGCAAGAAACCGCCAGAAGAGUGUACGUUCCCUGAGGGACAGCGUGAAAGGGCCUGUGGAAUCCAAGAGGGCGCUCUCCCUCCCUGAGACCCUGACCUCCAAAAUUCCUAUGAGGUUGACCAGGCAUGAGCAGUCUGCUCCAGCUCUCGGUGGGACACCCGAACAGACGCCAGGACAACAAUCUCCUGAGAAUGACAACACCAUCAAGGACCUGCUCCCAGAAGACGCUGGGAUCGACCACCAGACAGUUCACCAGCUGAUUACAGUGCUCAUGAAGUUCAUGGCCAAGGAUGAAAGCAGCGCUGAGUCAGACAUCAGCAGUGCAAAGGCCUUCAACACGGUCAAGCGACACCUGUACGUCUUACUCGGCUAUGACCAGCAGGAAGGUUGCUUCAUGAUUGCACCUCAAAAAAUGCGCCUGUCAACUUGCUUUAAUGCAUUCAUUGCAGGAAUUGCCCAAGUUAUGGACUAUAACAUUAACUUGGGAAAACACCUUCUCCCCUUAGUGGUUCAGGUGCUCAAAUACUGCUCUUGUCCUCAACUCCGGCAUUAUUUCCAACAGCCGCCUCGUUGCUCCCUCUGGUCCCUAAAGCCUCACAUCCGGCAGAUGUGGUUGAAGGCCUUGCUUGUCAUCCUUUACAAGUAUCCAUACCGAGACUGUGAUAUCAGCAAGAUCCUGCUGCAUCUGAUUCACAUAACAGUCAAUACACUCAAUGCGCAGUAUCAUAGCUGCAAGCCCCAUGCCACGGCAGGACCUUUGUACAGUGACAACAGUAACAUAAGCAGAUACAGCGAAAAAGAAAAAGAAGAAGAUAGUGUUUUUGAUGAAUCUGAUAUUCAUGAUACACCUACUGGACCCUGCAAUAAAGAGUCUCAAACUUUUUUUGCAAGAUUGAAAAGAAUAGGCGGCAGCAAAAUGGUGAAAUAUCAGCCGGUUGAGAUGAAUGUUCAGAGAAGUGAAAUAGAACUGGCUGAAUAUAGAGAGACGGGUGCAUUACAAGACAGCCUUCUCCACUGUGUGAGAGAAGAAAGCAUUCCGAAAAAAAAGCUACGCUCUUUCAAACAAAAAUCUCUUGAUAUAGGGAAUGCAGACUCGCUUUUGUUUACAUUAGACGAACAUCGUAGGAAGUCGUGCAUAGAUCGGUGUGACAUAGAGAAGCCUCCGACCCAAGCUGCGUAUAUCGCACAAAGACCAAACGACCCUGGACGUUCUAGACAGAACUCUGCUACGAGGCCUGACAAUAGUGAAAUCCCCGAGAACCCAGCUAUGGAAGGGUUUCCAGAUGCUCGAAGGCCUGUCAUACCAGAGGUUAGGUUAAACUGUAUGGAGACUUUCGAGGUGAAAGUUGACUCGCCGGUAAAGCCUGCUCCUAAAGAGGAUUUAGAUCUGAUAGAUCUAUCCUCAGAUUCAACCUCGGGGCCUGAAAAACACUCUAUACUCUCAACCUCCGACAGCGACUCUCUUGUAUUUGAGCCUCUUCCCCCUCUCAGAAUAGUCGAGAGUGACGAAGAAGAGGAGACGAUGAACCAAGGCGAUGACGGCCCCUCCGGUAAAAAUGCUGCCUCUUCUCCCUCCGUCCCCAGCCAUCCCUCCGUCCUCAGCCUGAGCACAGCUCCGCUUGUACAAGUAAGUGUGGAGGAUUGUUCCAAAGACUUUUCUUCUAAGGACUCAGGAAAUAAUCAGUCAGCAGGGAACACUGACUCUGCCCUCAUCACUCUGGAAGACCCUAUGGACGCCGAAGGAUCCUCAAAGCCAGAGGAGCUGCCAGAGUUCUCCUGCGGUAGCCCACUGACGCUGAAGCAAAAACGAGACCUCCUUCAGAAGUCGUUUGCUCUCCCCGAGAUGUCGCUGGAUGAUCACCCUGACCCGGGCACUGAGGGGGAGAAGCCUGGGGAGCUGAUGCCAAGUUCAGGGGCAAAAACCGUCCUCCUCAAAGUUCCCGAAGAUGCAGAGAACCCCACAGAAAGUGAGAAGCCUGAUACCAGUGCAGAAUCUGAUACAGAACAGAAUCCUGAAAGGAAGGUGGAAGAGGAUGGAGCUGAGGAAUCCGAAUUUAAGAUUCAGAUUGUUCCCAGGCAGAGGAAGCAGAGGAAGAUUGCUGUCAGUGCUAUCCAGAGAGAGUACCUCGACAUCUCCUUCAACAUUCUGGACAAACUGGGAGAACAGAAAGAUCCAGAUCCUUCUACUAAAGGACUUUCAACUUUGGAAAUGCCACGAGAAUCUUCAUCUGCCCCUACGUUAGAUGCAGGUGUGCCGGAAACAAGUAGCCAUUCCUCAAUAUCAACUCAGUAUAGGCAGAUGAAAAGGGGAUCCCUGGGAGUUCUGACAAUGAGCCAGUUAAUGAAGCGGCAGCUGGAGCAUCAGUCUAGCGCCCCCCAUAACAUCAGCAACUGGGACACUGAACAGAUACAGCCUGGGAAACGCCAGUGUAACGUGCCAACGUGCCUAAACCCUGACCUGGAGGGACAGCCAUUGAGGAUGAGAGGUGCCACCAAAUCCAGCCUGCUAUCAGCACCAAGCAUAGUCAGUAUGUUUGUGCCUGCACCUGAAGAGUUCACUGACGAGCAGCCGACGGUGAUGACGGACAAAUGCCAUGACUGUGGGGCCAUUCUUGAAGAAUACGAUGAAGAGACACUUGGGCUAGCCAUCGUGGUCCUCUCCACAUUCAUUCACUUAAGCCCAGACCUGGCAGCCCCGCUGCUGCUGGAUAUCAUGCAGUCUGUGGGAAGAUUGGCAUCCAGUACUACCUUUUCUAAUCAAGCAGAAAGCAUGAUGGUUCCCGGCAAUGCGGCGGGGGUGGCCAAGCAGUUCCUGCGCUGCAUCUUCCAUCAGUUGGCCCCCAACGGCAUCUUCCCGCAGCUGUUCCAAAGCACGAUCAAAGAUGGGACUUUUUUACGGACCUUAGCCUCGUCUCUGAUGGACUUCAAUGAGCUGAGCUCCAUCGCAGCUCUCAGUCAGCUCCUAGAGGGUCUAAAUAACAAAAAGAAUUUACCAGCAGGGGGUGCUAUGAUUCGCUGUUUGGAAAACAUUGCAACCUUCAUGGAAGCUUUGCCUAUGGAUUCUCCUAGUAGCCUCUGGACCACAAUUAGCAACCAGUUUCAGACAUUUUUUGCCAAGCUGCCUUGUGUUUUACCUCUGAAGUGUUCUUUAGAUUCCAGUUUAAGAAUUAUGAUUUGCCUCUUGAAGAUCCCUUCUACCAAUGCUACAAGGAGUUUGUUGGAACCAUUUUCAAAACUGCUCAGCUUUGUAAUUCAGAAUGCCGUCUUCACUCUGGCCUACCUGGUGGAGCUGUGUGGCUUAUGUUACCGAGCUUUCACUAAGGAACGAGAUAAAUUCUACUUGUCUCGUAGUGUUGUUCUAGAACUUCUGCAGGCCCUAAAGCUCAAAUCUCCUUUACCAGAUACAAACCUUCUUCUGCUUGUUCAGUUUAUUUGUGCAGAUGCUGGAACCAAACUAGCUGAGUCAACAAUCCUGAGCAAGCAGAUGAUAGCCUCUGUACCUGGAUGUGGGACUGCAGCGAUGGAGUGUGUGAGGCAGUACAUCAACGAAGUGCUGGAUUUCAUGGCAGACAUGCACACGCUGACCAAACUGAAGAGCCACAUGAAGACAUGUUCCCAGCCUCUGCAUGAAGAUACCUUUGGGGGACAUCUCAAAGUGGGGCUGGCCCAGAUUGCAGCCAUGGACAUCUCACGGGGCAACCACAGAGAUAACAAAGCUGUGAUCCGCUAUCUGCCUUGGCUUUAUCAUCCCCCCUCUGCAAUGCAGCAAGGACCUAAAGAAUUCAUUGAGUGUGUCUCCCAUAUCCGACUGUUGUCCUGGCUGCUGCUGGGUUCCCUCACUCACAAUGCAGUGUGCCCAAAUGCCUCCUCUCCCUGCCUGCCCAUUCCUCUGGAUGCAGGCUCCCACGUUGCAGACCAUCUUAUUGUUAUCCUGAUUGGAUUUCCAGAGCAAUCAAAGACCUCCGUGCUGCACAUGUGCUCCCUCUUCCACGCGUUCAUCUUUGCUCAGCUGUGGACAGUUUAUUGCGAGCAAAGUGCCGUCGCUACAAAUCUCCAAAAUCAGAAUGAAUUCAGCUUCACGGCGAUACUGACAGCACUAGAAUUUUGGAGUAGGGUGACACCCAGCAUCCUUCAGCUAAUGGCCCAUAACAAAGUGAUGGUAGAAAUGGUGUGUCUCCAUGUGAUUAGUUUAAUGGAGGCAUUGCAGGAAUGCAAUUCGACCAUUUUUGUCAAGCUGAUACCUAUGUGGUUGCCAAUGAUUCAGUCAAAUAUCAAGCACUUAUCUGCGGGACUCCAGCUUCGCCUCCAGGCUAUUCAGAACCACGUGAACCACCACAGCCUAAGGACGCUGCCGGGCUCGGGCCAGAGCAGUGCUGGCCUGGCAGCCCUCCGAAAGUGGUUGCAGUGCACUCAGUUCAAAAUGGCCCAGGUGGAGAUCCAGUCCUCGGAAGCAGCCUCUCAAUUUUAUCCUCUAUGAGUGGACUCCUCGGCGCUCAGUGUCAACACUCUGGUUUAGCAAUAAUGGGUUUAAAAACAAACAAUUUGAUCCAAGCAGGUUGGGGAACAUAUUGGUACUGUACAUUCUCUUUCUAGUUUAGUAAAAGAUGUGCAAAGGCCAGAGAGGGCCGAAAAUGAAGCUUUCUUGCUACACAUAUUUCUGAUGACUCCUUGGGCUAUCUGAUUAAGUGUUUCCUUACAUUAUUUUUUAAAAACCAAAUCAUUUUUCUUUAACUAACUUCUAUUUUUUUUAAGAAAAAAAAAUAGACUGGUGGGUACUCACAGAAAAGUUGUAUAAGUCCCCCUGUUGCUAUUUUUGAUGAUAGAGAAUAAAUAGGGUUUUUGAAACCUUUGUAGUGUUUUUUCUUAAAAUCCACUCUUGGCAAUGCAAUAAAAAAAACCGUCACCAUAAGCCAGUGACACCUGACUGAAGCUUUUUGUCUUUAUCCUGGGAAAAGUGGCAGCUUGCAAGGAACAUUACAAAGUGCACUUAGAAAUUAGGUGGUUAAACUGUGCCAAUUGUUUUCGUUGUUUUAUAAUAUCAUUUUCCAAAACUGUCCAGUAAGUUUUAUUAUUUUUAAAACUAGUUUUUCAACUCAUUAGUUCUAGGCUGUACUCUCUUGUAAGCUUUAUGAUAACCACUUUAGUUUUGUGAAUAAUAAAUUUUAUUCUUUUGUUAAUACUUGUAUACAAUUUAAUUGAAAACUGUAGCUUGCACACUGGACCAGAUGAGUCCCUCACUGGCACAGUGCCCUGCACCUGGAGUGAUGUUUCAUAAAACGGAAUUUUAAUAGUGUAAGAGCACCAAGAUUUCUCUGCACCUAUACCUAGCGUUGGACUGUGCAUUCCAAAUGAAAUUCCUCCUCUUUAUCCCUGUAAUGCACUGACUAACAGAAGACUUACUACACAUUUAAACUGUAUAUUGACAUGCUAUUAAAUGCGUUUUUUAUUA